GCCGCAUCUUCUCCAGCGCCCAGCCUCCCGCCCUCUCUCUUGCUGGCCGCACGCCCCGGCCCCGCGCACCUCCGCCCGGCUCCGCAGCCGCUACCCGCGCUUCGUUGCCCUGUGGGACUCCGAGCGAGCCCGGAGGGAACCCUCCUCUUCUUCUGGGGGCGACUUUUGUUUGCUUGCCUGUUUCUUUCUGGUGACUUUUGCAGCUUUCCAAUAUCCGUCUUCGGAGCGCACGGGAAUCCGCCGAGCUCUGCGUGCAGGCCCUUUUUUCUUUUGAGGUUCACAUUUUUUGAAAUUUUACGCCAGGGCUUUUGUAAUUUCCUCCCCCGCCCGCUGACGGUCCUGGAGUCGCUCGGGGCUUUAGGCCGGUUAUGCAACGUGUACCGCUCGGGGCUGCCGGCUGCACCUCCGCCGCGCCUCGCCGCUCACUGCGCUAGACCCGGCGCCCCGCGUCUCGCUUCGCGGGCAGUCAGGGGGCCGGCGCUCUGUCGAGGUCUCCAGCUAGAGCAGGGAGCCCGAGCCCGAGGGAGUCCCCGGAGCCGACGAAGGGCUUAUUAGACCCUGACUCUUUUCUGAGGCGCGCAGAUUUUGUCUUUGAUCACUCCCUCUCCGCGGGUCUACGGCCGCGCGCUUUCGGCGCCGGCGAUGGGGAGAAGACGGAGGCUGUGUCUCCAGCUCUACUUCCUGUGGCUGGGCUGUGUGGUGCUCUGGGCGCAGGGCACGGCCGGCCAGCCUCAGCCUCCUCCGCCCAAGCCGCCCCGGCCCCAGCCGCCGCCGCAACAGGUUCGGUCCGCUACAGCAGGCUCUGAAGGCGGGUUUCUAGCGCCCGAGUAUCGCGAGGAGGGUGCCGCAGUGGCCAGCCGCGUCCGCCGGCGAGGACAGCAGGACGUGCUCCGAGGGCCCAACGUGUGCGGCUCCAGAUUCCACUCCUACUGCUGCCCUGGAUGGAAGACGCUCCCUGGAGGAAACCAGUGCAUUGUCCCGAUUUGUAGAAAUAGUUGUGGAGAUGGAUUUUGUUCCCGUCCUAACAUGUGUACUUGUUCCAGUGGGCAAAUAUCAUCAACCUGUGGAUCAAAAUCAAUUCAGCAGUGCAGUGUGAGAUGCAUGAAUGGUGGGACCUGUGCAGAUGACCACUGCCAGUGCCAGAAAGGAUAUAUUGGAACUUAUUGUGGACAACCUGUCUGUGAAAAUGGAUGUCAGAAUGGUGGACGUUGCAUCGGACCCAACCGCUGUGCUUGUGUUUAUGGGUUCACUGGUCCACAGUGUGAAAGAGAUUACAGGACAGGCCCGUGUUUCACUCAGGUCAACAACCAGAUGUGCCAAGGGCAGCUGACAGGCAUUGUCUGCACGAAGACUCUGUGCUGUGCCACCAUUGGACGGGCGUGGGGCCAUCCCUGUGAGAUGUGUCCAGCCCAGCCUCAGCCCUGCCGACGGGGUUUCAUCCCCAACAUCCGCACUGGAGCUUGCCAAGAUGUUGAUGAAUGCCAGGCUAUCCCAGGGAUAUGCCAAGGAGGAAACUGUAUCAAUACAGUGGGCUCUUUUGAAUGCAGAUGCCCUGCUGGUCACAAACAGAGUGAAACUACUCAGAAAUGUGAAGACAUUGAUGAGUGCAGCAUCAUUCCUGGGAUAUGUGAAACUGGUGAAUGUUCCAACACCGUGGGAAGCUAUUUUUGUGUUUGUCCACGUGGAUAUGUAACCUCAACAGAUGGCUCUCGAUGCAUCGAUCAGAGAACAGGCAUGUGUUUCUCGGGCCUGGUGAAUGGCCGCUGUGCACAAGAGCUCCCGGGGAGAAUGACGAAAAUGCAGUGCUGCUGUGAGCCUGGCCGCUGCUGGGGCAUCGGAACCAUUCCUGAAGCCUGUCCUGUCAGAGGUUCUGAGGAAUAUCGCAGACUUUGCAUGGAUGGACUUCCAAUGGGAGGAAUUCCAGGGAGUGCUGGUUCCAGACCUGGAGGCACUGGGGGAAAUGGCUUUGCCCCAAGUGGCAAUGGCAAUGGCUAUGGCCCAGGAGGGACAGGCUUCAUCCCCAUCCCUGGAGGCAAUGGCUUUUCUCCUGGCGUUGGGGGAGCCGGUGUGGGGGCCGGGGGACAGGGACCUAUCAUCACUGGACUAACAAUUCUGAACCAGACAAUAGAUAUCUGUAAGCAUCAUGCUAACCUUUGUUUAAAUGGACGCUGUAUACCAACUGUCUCAAGCUACCGAUGUGAAUGCAACAUGGGUUAUAAGCAGGAUGCAAAUGGAGAUUGUAUAGAUGUUGAUGAAUGCACAUCAAAUCCCUGCACUAAUGGAGAUUGUGUUAACACACCUGGUUCCUAUUAUUGUAAAUGUCAUGCUGGAUUCCAGAGGACUCCUACCAAGCAAGCAUGCAUUGAUAUUGAUGAGUGCAUCCAGAAUGGGGUUCUUUGUAAAAACGGUCGAUGCGUGAACACAGAUGGAAGUUUCCAGUGCAUUUGCAAUGCCGGCUUUGAAUUAACUACAGAUGGAAAAAACUGUGUUGAUCAUGAUGAAUGUACAACUACCAACAUGUGUUUGAAUGGAAUGUGCAUCAAUGAAGAUGGCAGCUUCAAGUGCAUCUGCAAACCAGGAUUUGUCUUGGCUCCAAAUGGGCGUUACUGUACUGAUGUUGAUGAAUGCCAGACCCCAGGAAUCUGCAUGAAUGGGCACUGCAUCAACAGUGAAGGGUCCUUCCGCUGUGACUGUCCCCCAGGCCUGGCUGUGGGCAUGGAUGGACGUGUGUGUGUUGAUACUCACAUGCGCAGUACCUGCUAUGGAGGAAUCAAGAAAGGAGUGUGUGUGCGUCCUUUCCCCGGUGCAGUGACCAAGUCCGAAUGCUGCUGUGCCAAUCCAGACUAUGGUUUUGGAGAACCCUGCCAGCCAUGCCCUGCAAAAAAUUCAGCUGAAUUCCACGGCCUUUGUAGUAGUGGAGUAGGUAUCACUGUGGAUGGAAGAGAUAUCAAUGAAUGUGCUUUGGAUCCUGAUAUAUGUGCCAAUGGGAUUUGUGAAAACUUACGUGGUAGUUACCGUUGUAAUUGCAACAGUGGCUAUGAACCAGAUGCCUCUGGAAGAAACUGUAUUGACAUUGAUGAAUGUUUAGUAAACAGACUGCUUUGUGAUAACGGAUUGUGCCGAAACACGCCAGGAAGUUACAGCUGUACGUGCCCACCAGGGUAUGUGUUCAGGACUGAGACAGAGACCUGUGAAGAUAUAAAUGAAUGUGAAAGCAACCCAUGUGUCAAUGGGGCCUGCAGAAACAACCUUGGAUCUUUCAAUUGUGAAUGUUCGCCCGGCAGCAAACUCAGCUCCACAGGAUUGAUCUGUAUUGACAGCCUGAAGGGGACCUGUUGGCUCAACAUCCAGGACAGCCGCUGUGAGGUGAAUAUUAAUGGAGCCACUCUGAAAUCUGAAUGCUGUGCCACCCUCGGAGCCGCCUGGGGGAGCCCCUGUGAGCGGUGUGAACUAGAUACAGCUUGCCCAAGAGGGCUUGCCAGGAUUAAAGGUGUUACGUGUGAAGAUGUUAAUGAGUGUGAGGUGUUCCCUGGCGUUUGUCCAAAUGGACGCUGUGUCAACAGUAAGGGAUCUUUUCAUUGCGAGUGCCCUGAAGGCCUUACGUUGGAUGGGACUGGCCGUGUAUGUUUGGAUAUUCGCAUGGAGCAGUGUUACUUGAAGUGGGAUGAAGAUGAAUGCAUCCACCCCGUUCCUGGAAAGUUCCGCAUGGAUGCCUGCUGCUGUGCUGUCGGGGCGGCUUGGGGCACCGAGUGUGAGGAGUGCCCCAAACCUGGCACCAAGGAAUACGAGACGCUGUGCCCCCGCGGGGCUGGCUUUGCUAACCGAGGGGAUGUUCUUACUGGGCGGCCAUUUUACAAAGACAUCAAUGAAUGCAAAGCAUUUCCUGGGAUGUGCACUUAUGGGAAGUGCAGAAAUACAAUCGGAAGCUUCAAAUGCCGUUGCAAUAGUGGCUUUGCUCUAGACAUGGAGGAAAGAAACUGCACGGACAUCGACGAGUGCAGGAUUUCUCCUGACCUCUGUGGCAGUGGAAUCUGCGUCAAUACACCGGGCAGCUUUGAGUGCGAGUGCUUCGAAGGCUAUGAAAGUGGCUUCAUGAUGAUGAAGAACUGCAUGGACAUUGACGAAUGUGAACGUAACCCUCUCCUUUGUAGGGGUGGCACCUGUGUGAACACUGAGGGCAGCUUUCAGUGUGACUGCCCACUGGGACACGAGCUGUCACCAUCCCGUGAGGACUGUGUGGAUAUUAAUGAAUGCUCCCUGAGUGACAAUCUCUGCAGAAAUGGAAAAUGUGUGAACAUGAUUGGAACCUAUCAGUGCUCUUGCAAUCCUGGAUAUCAGGCUACGCCAGACCGCCAGGGCUGUACAGAUAUUGAUGAAUGUAUGAUAAUGAACGGAGGCUGUGACACCCAGUGCACAAAUUCAGAGGGAAGCUACGAAUGCAGCUGCAGUGAGGGUUAUGCCCUGAUGCCAGAUGGGAGAUCGUGUGCAGACAUUGAUGAAUGUGAAAACAAUCCUGAUAUCUGUGAUGGCGGCCAGUGUACCAACAUUCCUGGAGAGUAUCGCUGCCUCUGCUAUGAUGGCUUCAUGGCUUCCAUGGACAUGAAAACAUGCAUUGAUGUCAAUGAAUGUGACCUAAAUUCAAAUAUCUGCAUGUUUGGGGAAUGUGAGAACACAAAGGGAUCCUUCAUUUGCCACUGUCAGCUGGGUUACUCAGUGAAGAAGGGGACCACAGGAUGUACAGAUGUGGAUGAGUGUGAAAUUGGUGCUCAUAACUGCGACAUGCAUGCCUCAUGUCUGAAUAUCCCAGGAAGCUUCAAGUGUAGCUGCAGAGAAGGCUGGAUUGGAAACGGCAUCAAGUGUAUUGAUCUGGACGAAUGUUCUAAUGGAACCCACCAGUGUAGCAUCAAUGCUCAGUGUGUAAAUACCCCGGGCUCAUACCGCUGUGCCUGCUCCGAAGGUUUCACUGGUGAUGGCUUUACCUGCUCAGAUGUUGAUGAGUGUGCAGAAAACAUAAACCUCUGUGAGAACGGACAGUGCCUUAAUGUCCCGGGUGCAUAUCGCUGCGAGUGUGAGAUGGGCUUCACUCCAGCCUCAGACAGCAGAUCCUGCCAAGAUAUUGAUGAAUGCUCCUUCCAAAACAUUUGUGUCUUUGGAACAUGUAAUAACCUGCCUGGAAUGUUUCAUUGCAUCUGCGAUGAUGGUUAUGAAUUGGACAGAACAGGAGGGAACUGUACAGAUAUUGAUGAGUGUGCAGAUCCUAUAAACUGUGUCAAUGGCCUAUGUGUCAACACGCCUGGUCGCUAUGAGUGUAACUGCCCACCCGAUUUUCAGUUGAACCCAACUGGUGUGGGUUGUGUUGACAACCGUGUGGGCAACUGCUACCUGAAGUUUGGACCUCGAGGAGAUGGGAGUCUGUCUUGCAACACCGAGAUCGGGGUGGGCGUCAGUCGCUCUUCAUGCUGCUGCUCUCUGGGAAAGGCCUGGGGAAACCCCUGUGAGACAUGCCCCCCUGUCAAUAGCACUGAAUAUUACACCCUGUGUCCCGGAGGUGAAGGCUUCAGACCUAACCCCAUCACAAUCAUUUUAGAAGACAUUGACGAAUGCCAGGAGUUACCAGGUCUCUGCCAGGGUGGAAACUGCAUCAACACUUUUGGGAGCUUCCAGUGUGAGUGCCCACAAGGCUACUACCUCAGCGAGGAUACCCGCAUCUGUGAAGAUAUUGAUGAGUGUUUUGCACAUCCUGGUGUGUGUGGGCCUGGGACCUGCUAUAACACCCUGGGAAAUUACACCUGCAUUUGCCCACCUGAGUACAUGCAGGUCAAUGGAGGCCACAACUGCAUGGACAUGAGAAAAAGCUUUUGCUACCGAAGCUAUAAUGGAACCACUUGUGAGAAUGAGUUGCCUUUCAAUGUGACAAAAAGGAUGUGCUGCUGCACAUAUAAUGUGGGCAAAGCCUGGAACAAACCUUGUGAACCAUGCCCAACUCCAGGAACAGCUGACUUUAAAACCAUAUGUGGAAAUAUUCCUGGAUUCACCUUUGACAUUCACACAGGAAAAGCUGUUGACAUUGAUGAAUGUAAAGAGAUUCCAGGCAUUUGUGCAAAUGGUGUGUGCAUUAACCAGAUUGGCAGUUUCCGCUGUGAAUGCCCUACAGGAUUCAGUUACAAUGACCUGCUGUUGGUUUGUGAAGAUAUAGAUGAGUGCAGCAAUGGUGAUAAUCUCUGCCAGCGGAAUGCAGACUGCAUCAAUAGUCCUGGUAGUUACCGCUGUGAAUGUGCCGCGGGUUUCAAACUUUCACCCAAUGGGGCCUGUGUAGAUCGCAAUGAAUGUUUAGAAAUUCCUAACGUUUGCAGUCAUGGCUUGUGUGUUGAUCUGCAAGGAAGUUACCAGUGCAUCUGCCACAAUGGCUUUAAGGCUUCUCAGGACCAGACCAUGUGCAUGGAUGUUGAUGAGUGCGAGCGGCAUCCAUGUGGAAAUGGAACUUGUAAAAACACCGUUGGAUCCUAUAACUGUCUGUGCUACCCAGGGUUUGAACUCACUCAUAAUAAUGAUUGCCUGGACAUAGAUGAGUGCAGUUCCUUUUUUGGUCAGGUGUGCAGAAAUGGACGUUGUUUUAAUGAAAUUGGUUCUUUCAAGUGUCUAUGUAACGAAGGUUAUGAACUUACCCCAGAUGGCAAAAACUGUAUAGACACUAAUGAGUGUGUCGCCCUUCCCGGCUCUUGCUCUCCUGGUACCUGUCAGAAUUUGGAGGGAUCCUUCAGAUGCAUCUGUCCCCCAGGGUAUGAAGUAAAAAGCGAGAACUGCAUUGAUAUAAAUGAAUGUGAUGAAGAUCCCAACAUUUGUCUUUUUGGUUCCUGUACUAAUACUCCAGGGGGCUUCCAGUGCCUCUGCCCCCCUGGCUUUGUACUAUCUGAUAAUGGACGGAGAUGCUUUGAUACUCGCCAGAGCUUCUGCUUCACAAAUUUUGAAAAUGGAAAGUGUUCUGUACCCAAAGCUUUCAACACCACAAAAGCAAAAUGCUGCUGUAGUAAGAUGCCAGGAGAGGGCUGGGGGGACCCCUGUGAGCUGUGCCCCAAAGACGAUGAAGUUGCAUUUCAGGAUUUGUGUCCAUAUGGCCAUGGAACUGUCCCUAGUCUUCAUGAUACACGUGAAGAUGUCAAUGAGUGUCUUGAGAGCCCAGGCAUUUGUUCAAAUGGUCAAUGUAUCAACACCGACGGAUCUUUUCGCUGUGAAUGUCCAAUGGGCUACAACCUUGACUACACUGGAGUACGCUGUGUGGAUACUGAUGAGUGUUCAAUCGGCAAUCCGUGUGGAAAUGGUACAUGCACCAAUGUUAUUGGGAGUUUUGAAUGCAAUUGCAAUGAAGGCUUUGAGCCAGGGCCCAUGAUGAAUUGUGAAGAUAUCAACGAAUGUGCCCAGAACCCACUGCUGUGUGCUUUCCGCUGCAUGAACACUUUUGGGUCCUAUGAAUGCACGUGCCCGAUUGGCUAUGCCCUCAGGGAAGAUCAAAAGAUGUGCAAAGAUCUGGAUGAAUGUGCUGAAGGGUUACACGACUGUGAAUCUAGGGGCAUGAUGUGUAAGAAUCUAAUCGGCACCUUCAUGUGCAUCUGCCCUCCUGGAAUGGCCCGAAGGCCCGAUGGAGAAGGCUGUGUAGAUGAAAAUGAAUGCAGGACCAAGCCAGGAAUCUGUGAAAAUGGACGUUGUGUUAACAUUAUUGGAAGCUAUAGAUGUGAGUGUAAUGAAGGAUUCCAGUCAAGUUCUUCAGGCACUGAAUGCCUUGACAAUCGACAGGGUCUCUGCUUUGCAGAGGUACUGCAGACAAUAUGUCAAAUGGCAUCCAGUAGUCGCAAUCUCGUCACUAAGUCAGAAUGCUGCUGUGAUGGUGGGCGAGGCUGGGGCCACCAGUGCGAGCUUUGCCCACUUCCUGGAACUGCCCAGUACAAAAAGAUAUGUCCUCAUGGCCCAGGAUAUACAACUGAUGGAAGAGAUAUUGAUGAAUGUAAGGUAAUGCCAAACCUCUGCACCAAUGGUCAGUGCAUCAAUACCAUGGGCUCAUUCCGAUGCUUCUGCAAGGUUGGCUACACCACAGACAUCAGUGGAACCUCUUGUAUAGACCUUGAUGAAUGCUCCCAGUCCCCGAAACCAUGCAACUACAUCUGCAAGAACACUGAGGGGAGUUAUCAGUGUUCAUGUCCGAGGGGGUAUGUCCUGCAAGAGGAUGGAAAGACAUGCAAAGACCUUGAUGAAUGUCAAACAAAGCAGCAUAACUGCCAGUUCCUCUGUGUCAACACCCUGGGGGGGUUUACCUGUAAAUGUCCACCUGGUUUCACACAGCAUCACACUGCUUGUAUCGACAACAACGAAUGUGGGUCUCAACCUUCGCUUUGUGGAGCAAAGGGAAUCUGUCAAAACACUCCAGGCAGUUUCAGCUGUGAAUGCCAAAGAGGGUUCUCUCUUGAUGCCACCGGACUGAACUGUGAAGAUGUUGAUGAAUGUGAUGGGAACCACAGGUGCCAACACGGCUGCCAGAACAUCCUGGGUGGCUACAGAUGUGGCUGCCCCCAAGGCUACAUCCAGCACUACCAGUGGAAUCAGUGUGUCGAUGAGAAUGAAUGCUCCAAUCCCAAUGCCUGUGGCUCUGCUUCCUGCUACAACACCCUGGGGAGUUACAAGUGCGCCUGCCCCUCGGGGUUCUCCUUCGACCAGUUCUCCAGUGCCUGCCACGACGUGAAUGAGUGCUCGUCCUCCAAGAACCCCUGCAAUUACGGCUGCUCUAACACGGAGGGGGGCUACCUCUGUGGCUGCCCCCCUGGGUAUUACAGAGUGGGACAAGGCCACUGUGUCUCAGGAAUGGGAUUUAACAAGGGGCAGUACCUGUCACUGGAUACAGAGGUCGAUGAGGAAAAUGCUCUGUCCCCAGAAGCAUGCUACGAGUGCAAAAUCAACGGCUAUUCUAAGAAAGACAGCAGGCAGAAGAGAAGUAUUCAUGAACCUGAUCCCACUGCUGUUGAACAGAUCAGCCUAGAGAGUGUCGACAUGGACAGCCCCGUCAACAUGAAGUUCAACCUCUCCCACCUCGGCUCUAAGGAGCACAUCCUGGAACUAAGGCCCGCCAUCCAGCCCCUCAACAACCACAUCCGUUAUGUCAUCUCUCAAGGGAACGAUGACAGCGUCUUCCGCAUCCACCAAAGGAAUGGGCUCAGCUACUUGCACACGGCCAAGAAGAAGCUCAUGCCCGGCACAUACACACUGGAAAUCACUAGCAUCCCUCUCUACAAGAAGAAGGAGCUUAAGAAACUGGAAGAGAGCAAUGAGGAUGACUACCUCCUAGGGGAGCUUGGGGAGGCUCUCAGAAUGAGGCUGCAGAUUCAGCUCUAUUAACCCUUCACAGACUUGGGCCCAGGCUCAAAUCCUAGCACAGCCAGUCUGCAGAAGCAUUUGAAAAGUCAAGGACUAAUUUUAAAGAGGAAAAAUAAUAAUAACUCUUGUUUCUUUCCUCCCUGUCUUAGACUUUGAAUGUUGACCCUCACAGGGAGGGAUAAUUUAGACUCUGGUAUGGCCAAAGAUUUGAGCACAAAGGCAACCGUGGUUACUGUAUUUUUUAUAUAACUUCAUUUUAAAAUAUAUUAAAAGAAACCUAAAUGUUCAAGAUAUCAGCAUAUGGCACUAAAUGCACAAAAAUAAUGUGAGCUUUUUUUUUUUUUCCUGUUAGCAGUCUGUAACACUUUGGGUAUUUUGCUAUAGUUGCUAAUUAAAAAAAUAUAGAUGUUUAUUUAUUUUUAAUGCAGUAAUAUAUGGAGAAAUGAACAAACUAUGUAAACAAAAAGGGAAACUCACUUGUUUUUCUUUAGAUUUAUAAAUUUGAGCUAUUUUUUUUAGAGGUGCUUUUUAAAAAUCCAAUAGAUACAAGAGAUGUUUCCUUUGGUUUUCUGCCAGUCAUCCAGCUGAUACACACCUGAUGAUUUUAAAGAAAGCCACACAGAGCUGAAUGGGCAGUGUAAUCAAUAAUUUAAAAAACAUGAAUGUCAUUAGAUCCUUUAUAACGUAGAUCGAAGCCAAAGCAGCUCAUUUGUGACAACAUUUCAUAUCACCAGACACACCAGGCAACAGAAGUUGAAGCACAACCACUGUAGCAAAAUACCUUGACUGCUUGUGAGACCAUUAGCAUUGCAGGCCAAACCGUACUGUAUUUCCUUCUCAUAACCUCAAGGAACCAUAUGUGCUACCCACAACACCUCAUUCUUACCCAGGGUGCGCUGCGUCCUCAUGGUACUGUAGGCAGCUGAAGAACCGCCGUUCCCUUGAAAGGGAACACCUGGCAUUCUGUGGUGUUUCGUGCUGUCUUAAAUAAUGGUGCAUUUAUUAUGUUCAAGUUAUUUCAGGAUUGCCAUAUGUGCAAACAAAUCAUGCAAUGCAGCCAAGGAAUAUAUGUUGUUGUUGUUGUUUUAAACCCAUUUUUUUUUUAGAAUUUUCAUUAAUACUGUAGUUAUACACCAUAUGCCUCAUUUUAUCAUAGCCUAUUGUGUAUGAAAGAUGUUUGUACAAUGAAUUGAUGUUUAGUUUGCUUUAGUCAUUUAAAAAGAUAUUGUACCAGGAUGUGCUAUUAAGAGCACGUAUCCAUUAUUCUUCUCAACCCAAGAACCUGUUUCCUGGACCAGUGACCAAACCUCAUAUGUGAAAUGGCCAAAGCACAUGCAGGCUCCUGGUUGUUCCUCUCAAACCUGUGCUGACCAAAGAUUAGUAACCAGUUAUACCCAGUAUUUUGAGGUUUUAUUGUUUUUUUAAUAACUAAAAAGAAAAAAGGAACAGUGUAAAUUUGUAAUCAAGAGUUUGUGAGGAAAAACUUAUGGUUUUUGGUUUUGUUUGUUUUUGUAGGUCUGUGUAUCAAAUAUGACACUUUUCUUGCAAUAAAGCUUAUUUUGGGGUA